AGUCCACGCCUUGUGGCGGCUUUGCGGAGCUGCUGCUUUGGCGGGAGUUGGAAGCUGGUGUGAGGUGAGAGGCGCGGUGGUCGCUCCCCGGCGAGGCCAGGUUUCUGUGGGGAGAAGGAGAGUGCCAGAGGUGACUGGUUCGUGGUUCUUCUAGGCUCUCAUGGCCACCAUGUUGGAAGGCAGAUGCCAAACUCAGCCAAGGAGCAGCCCCAGUGGCCGAGAGGCUAGCCUGUGGUCGUCAGGCUUUGGGAUGAAGCUGGAGGCUGUCACUCCAUUCCUGGGCAAGUAUCGCCCCUUUGUGGGUCGCUGUUGCCAGACCUGCACCCCCAAGAGCUGGGAGUCCCUCUUCCACAGAAGCAUAACGGACCUAGGCUUCUGCAAUGUGAUCCUGGUGAAGGAGGAGAACACAAGGUUUCGGGGCUGGCUGGUUCGGAGGCUCUGCUAUUUCCUGUGGUCCCUGGAGCAGCACAUCCCCCCCUGCCAGGAUGUCCCACAGAAGAUCAUGGAAAGCACCGGGGUGCAGAACCUCCUCUCAGGGAGGGUCCCAGGAGGCACUGGGGAAGGCCAGGUGCCUGACCUUGUGAAGAAGGAGGUACAGCGCAUCCUGGGUCACAUCCAGGCCCCACCCCGUCCCUUCCUGGUCAGGCUGUUCAGCUGGGCGCUGCUGAGGUUCCUGAACUGCCUGUUCCUGAAUGUGCAGCUCCACAAGGGUCAGAUGAAGAUGGUCCAGAAGGCCGCCCAGGCAGGCUUGCCGCUUGUCCUCCUCUCUACUCACAAAACCCUCCUGGAUGGGAUCCUGCUGCCCUUUAUGCUGCUCUCCCAGGGCCUGGGUGUGCUUCGUGUGGCCUGGGACUCCCGCGCCUGCUCCCCUGCCCUCAGAGCUCUGCUGAGGAAGCUUGGGGGGCUUUUCCUGCCCCCAGAGGCCAGCCUCUCCCUGGACAGCUCUGAGGGGCUCCUUGCCAGGGCUGUGGUCCAGGCGGUCAUAGAGCAGCUGCUGGUUAGUGGGCAGCCCCUGCUCAUCUUCCUGGAGGAACCUCCUGGGGCUCUGGGGCCACGGCUGUCAGCCCUGGGCCAGGCUUGGGUGGGGUUUGUGGUGCAGGCAGUCCAGGUGGGCAUCGUCCCAGAUGCUCUGCUGGUACCAGUGGCCGUCACCUAUGACCUGGUUCCGGAUGCACCGUGUGACAUAGACCAUGCCUCGGCCCCCCUGGGGCUGUGGACAGGAGCUCUGGCUGUCCUACGUAGCUUGUGGAGCCGCUGGGGCUGCAGCCACCGGAUCUGCUCCUGGGUGCGCCUAGCUCAGCCCUUUUCCCUGCAGGAAUACAUCGUCAGUGCCAGAAGCUGCUGGGGCGGCAGACAGACCCUGGAGCAGCUACUGCAGCCCAUCAUGCUGGGCCAAUGUACUGCUGUCCCAGACACUGAGAAGGAGCAGGAGUGGACCCCCAUAACUGGGCCUCUCCUGGCCCUCAAGGAAGAGGACCAGCUCCUGGUCAGGAGACUGAGCUGUCAUGUCCUGAGUGCCAGUGUGGGGAGCUCUGCGGUGAUGAGCACGGCCAUCAUGGCGACGCUGCUGCUCUUCAAGCAUCAGAAGGGUGUGUUCCUGUAGCAGCUCCUAGGGGAGUUCUCCUGGCUGACGGAGGAGAUACUGUUGCGUGACUUUGAUGUAGGCUUCUCUGGGCAGCUGUGGAGCCUGCUGCAGCACUCACUGAGCCUGCUGCGGGCACACGUGGCCCUGCUGCGCAUCCGCCAGGGCGACUUGCUGGUGGUGCCACGGCCUGGCCCAGGCCUCACACACCUCACGGCAUGGCUGAGUGCUGAGCUGCUGCCCAUCUUCCUGAGCGAGGCUGUGGGCGGUGAGUCUUGAGGUGCACGGGGG